AGUUUCCCGAGGUACCUAGUGUCUGAGCGGCACAGACGAGAUCUCGAUCGAAGGCGAGAUGGCGGACGUGCUAGAUCUUCACGAGGCUGGGGGCGAAGAUUUCGCCAUGGAUGAGGAUGGGGACGAGAGCAUUCACAAACUGAAAGAAAAAGCGAAGAAACGGAAGGGUCGCGGCUUUGGCUCCGAAGAGGGGUCCCGAGCGCGGAUGCGUGAGGAUUAUGACAGCGUGGAGCAGGAUGGCGAUGAACCCGGACCACAACGCUCUGUUGAAGGCUGGAUUCUCUUUGUAACUGGAGUCCAUGAGGAAGCCACCGAAGAAGACAUACACGACAAAUUCGCAGAAUAUGGGGAAAUUAAAAACAUUCAUCUCAACCUCGACAGGCGAACAGGAUAUCUGAAGGGGUAUACUCUAGUUGAAUAUGAAACAUACAAGGAAGCCCAGGCUGCUAUGGAGGGACUCAAUGGCCAGGAUUUGAUGGGACAGCCCAUCAGCGUUGACUGGUGUUUUGUUCGGGGUCCACCAAAAGGCAAGAGGAGAGGUGGCCGAAGACGCAGCAGAAGUCCAGACCGGAGACGUCGCUGACAGGUCCUCUGUUGUCCAGGUGUUCUCUUCAAGAUUCCAUUUGACCAUGCAGCCUUGGACAAAUAGGACUGGGGUGGAACUUGCUGUGUUUAUAUUUAAUCUCUUACCGUAUAUGCGUAGUAUUUGAGUUGCGAAUAAAUGUUCCAUUUUUGUUUUCUACAUUUAAUGUUACUUUCCUGUCCUAAAAUUGAAAGUUCUAAAGCAUAGCAAGGCUGUAUGGAUCAUUGUGAAGAUACUUCUAGGGACUGAACUCUAUGUAUUUCUUUUUUUUCUUUUUUUUGAGAUAGAGUCUUGCUGUGUUACCCAGGGUGGAUUGCAGCUGAUCAUAGCUCACUGCAGCUUCAAACUCUUGGGCUCAAGCCAUCCUUCUGCCUCACUGUCCCUAGUAGUUGGGAUUACAGGCACAUGCCACCAUGCCCAGCUAAAUUUUUAAUAUUUUUGUAGAGAUGGGGUCUUGCUGUGUUACCUGGGCUAGUUAUGUGAGUUUCUAUAUUAGACAUAGUCUCAAGUUUCAGGUAGGGUUUAAAGUAGAGACACUGGUCAGUAUUUCUUUUUUGGGGGGAACUAGGAGAGCAGGAGUAGAAGUGAGAUGUUAAGAUCUUAUGGCACUAAAGACUUACUAUUCUGUUCCUACAUACUCUGUUAGGAUCAGAUAGAUGUUAUAGAAAUGCCUUUUGUUUCUCCUGCCCUUCUUGAUGUCACAGUUUUUUGUACUUCCAGCUGUCUAAAGGCAUGAAUCUCCUCUUGGAGCAUUCUCCCAGACCCUUCUUUAGAAGAGUCUAUACUAAGUUCUUGGUGCCCUCUUCGGCAGCCAAGGGUGAAGGCCCCAUAGAGGAGAGGAUCCAAAGGAGCAUUGAGGAGGCCCAAGAGGAAAAGGAUGUGGCUCAGGCUGGGAGGGACUUCAGUUAGCAUGGUGGGGGAGAACCAGUACCACAUACCCAGUAGGUAAUAAGGUGUCCAGCAGAGGAUGAAGGUCAGCAAGAUAAGCAGGGCCAGUCUCAGGGCCCGGAGACGAACACGGGGACAAUUGUCAAAGGAGCGGGGGAGGGCAAAUUCACCAGCAGGGGCUAGGAAUUUAGAAAAUAUACUGUAAUUCAGACACUCAGCUUCUGAUCUGAGUAUAGGGUGAAUUGAUGGAGGGGCAUAGCUAGUGAGACAGAGCUCGCCUCCUACAAGGAGGAGAAUGUUGCAAACCGUUUUCCCCUUCCCAACCUGGGACUAUAUGAUUUCUUACCCCCAGGGAUUAUGAUAGAAAUAUGAAGCCACCAAGUCUAGACUUGAUGGUGUUCAAGAAUAAAUAAUACUGAUUGCCUCCCUAGUCCUUGUCCAGCUAACUCAGCUGUUUAUAAUUGAAGGGAUUCAACAAAAUUAUCUCUAGCAUCAGGUGCUAGACAUGGUUAGAAUCUCACCAUGGUUUAGUGACUGGUAGAUAGCUAUUAGGUAGGUAGAUAAAUAAAUGAUGCUAGAGGCAACAGGUCUAGGGUUAAGGAUUAAGGCCUGGGAAUUGGAGUCUCACCAUGGCUCCCCUUCCUUGUCUGGGGCCUGGACACACUGAGGACAAUGCGGCUAUAGCAGAUGGCCAUGGCAGUCAGUGGCAGCAGAAAGAGGCAGCAGAAGGUGAAGAGGUUAUAGGUGGUCUCUUGCCAUUGAGCCUUGAAGCUGCCUUUGGUGACACACUGAGUGAAAGGGACUGGGCCAGCUCAGUGGACCGUGUGGAACAGGAACAGCUGGAGUGGAGUUGAGGACUAUUAGAACUGGUUCCCCUCACCACCCAACCUACCCACCUAUGUCAUACUGUCUCCUCCCAAUUCAUCCUUAAUUCCAAGUGAAGCAGCACAGUGCUGAGAAACAGUUCAUCCAUGGUGCCAUGUUAAAGAAGUUGGAAAUAUAUCUUGAAAAUCCUAUCUUCCUUUUAGGCUUGAAUAUGAUGCUGAACAGUAAGUUUGUUAAAUCUUGGAACUUAAAACAAUCCUGCUUUCUCAAGUACUAUUCUAACAUUGCGCUUUAUAAGGGAUGAUAUUUCUACCACCUCACUCAUAUUUUUAGCUGAAAUGAUUUUCCUGGUAUGUCUGUUAUUUUGUGGAAAAAGAAAUAUUGUGUAAAAUGGGUGCUGCCAAAAUUCCAGGCCAUUUUGCAGGGACUCUGAAGUGACCUUUAGUAGUAAUAGUCUUAUGUGCAGUAACUAUAAUGGUAAAGAAUGUUAAAUAAUAAAAUUUAACAUUUUCCAAAUGCUAUUGGGCUGCCCCUCCCCCUUUUUGUUAAAUUGCUGGGUUUUCCAACUGAAUCAGUAAAAACUAUUUCUGUUUAGAGCUACAAGGUUAAAGUGCCUGCUUUCCAGUAAUGGAGAUUGAGUCACUAUUAAUUUGAUAAAAGGUAAGCUCAGUAGGCAUCAGAUUCCUAGAUACAAGGCAUUUGGGAAAGUGAUUUUAGCAGACAUGAGGGACAUUUAGGAAAGAUGAAUAGUUUCAGCCUAAGAGAAUUUUGUGAACUGUUUGGAGUUACGAUCAGGCUACUCUGAGCUAGUUGGGAAAUGGUCUUUCCUCUUCCCAUCUCUUGCAUUCAUAUAUUUCUAAGUUUUUUUUUUUGUUUUUGUUUUUGUGCUCUGCCUAAGAAGUGCUUGAGAAUUGUGAGGAGUAUAAAAAUAGUCAAAGCUGGCUGGGCGCGGUGGCUCACGCCUGUAAUCCCAGCACUUUGGGAGGCUGAGGCGGGCGGAUCACGAGGUUAGGAGAUGGAGACCAUCCUGGCUAACACAGUGAAACCCUGUCUGUACUAAAGAUACAAAAAACUAGCCGGGCGUGGUGGUAGGUGCCUGUAGUCCCAGCUACUUGGGAACUCGGGAGGCUGAGGCAGGAGAAUGACCUGAACCCAGGAGGCGGAGCUUGCAGUGAGCAGAGAUUGCGCCAUUGCACUCCAGCCUGGGCGACAGAGUAAGACUGUCUCCAAAAAAAAAAAAAAUAAUAAUCAAAGCUCUUGGAUUUAUAGUUUGGUCCACAGCCUUGUUUUGAUCUUUCCUUUAUCCUGUUUUAUUGCCAUUUACCACGUACUGUAGAAACAUCCCUUUCAACUGCUGAUAACUUGGAAACAAGCCUACAAAAAUAAGUAAUUUCUAACUACUCCUAAUACUACCUAUAACUACCCCUAAGCCCUUACCACUCUAACGUGACAUUAUUAAAUUUUUUAUUUUAUUAACACUAAUAUUUUAACUACAAUUACAGCAUAUGGGCAAUACAGAAUUUACCUAAAAGGAUACUAAUUUGGAACAAAAAAAAUCACCUUUCGCACAUGUAUCAUGUCACAACCAGUUUGCCAUUGAAACAAAUAGAGGUUGCAAAUAUUGUCAGAUUGUCAGGCUGUAAGAAAGGAUGAAAUUCAUUUCCCAUUGCAUCAUCUUGUGGCCCAUGGAUUUCAAGUGCCUUAGCCAAAAUCAUAUAGCUAGUUAGCAGUAGAGCCGAGACUCAGAAAAAAACAAAGUAAAACAGGCAGACUGAAACAAAAAGUCUUCUAAUUCCCAGUCCACAUGUAAAAUUUGCUUCAUAUAAACAAACCUAAUUGUAAAUGGCACUGUAGCAACAGGCUUCUUUUUAACACUUGGAUUGGUAAAGGUCUUGUUUGCAACAUAUUAGAAGUAUUAUUUUUCUCUUUCCCCCCCACCCCACCCCCAACAGAGUCUGGCUCUGCCGCCCACGCCGGAGUGCAGUGGUGCAGUCUUGGCUCACUGCAGCCUCCACUUCCCAGGUUCAAGCAAUUCUCGUGCCUCAGCCUCCUGAGUAGUUGGGAUUACAGGUGCUCACCACUAUACCCGGCUAAUUUUUGUAUUUUUAGUAGAGAUGGGGUUUCGUCAUGUUGGCCAGGUUGGUCUUAAACUCCUGACCUCAAGUGAUCCACCCACCUUGGCCUUCCAAAAUGCUGGGAUUACAGGCUUGAGCCACCAGGCCUUUCUUUGUUCUUAGGAGUAUAGUCAGACUAACUUCUAGUAGUUAUAUUUCUAAUAAUUGAGGAUGUAAGUAAGGAUCAAAUCUUAAAUCAGUAUAAUGCAUUGUCAUUCCAGAGAUAAAUCCUAGACCCUUCUUGGCCUCCUUCUGACAUAAUUCUAAUCCUACAGUCUCAGAGAUGCUGUUGUAUCCUGCCCCCCAACCCCAUGAUAGUGAUAGUGGUUUUUGCCUUGAAGGAAUUGCUUUGUAUUUAGCUUUUCCCCCUCUAGAUUUCUAGUUCCUUUUCAGUAUUGGAUUGGAUUUGAGAUUUGAUUAACCUAGUACUCAGGUUCAGAUGCUCGCCUCUUUGCAAUUUUAACACUCAUUCGACAAUAAAGUCAGUAAAAAACACAAA